CGCUCUCUCCUCACUCCCUGGCGCUCUCUCGCUCUAGCUCUCUCUCUCGCUCGCUCUCUCUCGCUCUCACCCUCGCUCUGCGUUCUGUCCGGGAGGAGUACGAAGAAGCCAAUAGGAUGCGGGGUCUCUAAUGGAUGCAAAUGAUCAUGAAAAGACAGUGCAAAAUAUGAAACAACUCAUUUGCAGGGAAGUAAAUCACCGAAAACUGUUUAUGAACUGGCAUCCCUUCUUCGAAAUGUAAAGCGAGGACCUCUUUAAGUGGUGGUAUAUUUUUGUUUGGGGGGUGGGGGGUGGGGGGAGGGCGAGCGAGCCGCGGCUGCCAUGCAAGCUUAGACUUUUGGAGGCUUCUCUGUCCUUUUCUAUUCCUGGAAACCACAAAAAGUGUGUCGGCUUCGAGAUCUUCUUCGCCUUUUCUUUCUUUUCUUUUUUUCCCUCCUCUCUUUCCCUCUCCUUUCCUGGCGAGGGUGACUAGGAGCCGGCGAAUCCGCGUUUUUUUCUCUCUCUCCCUCCCUUUCCCCCUCCCCACCCCCUCCCCAACAGCCCCCAACUAUAGCCUCCGCCGCCGCCGCCGCCUCAAAAUUCAAUAAAAUGAGCUCUUAUUUCGUCAACUCACUGUUCUCCAAAUACAAAACCGGGGAGUCCCUGCGCCCCAAUUAUUAUGACUGCGGCUUCGCCCAGGACCUGGGCGGCCGACCCACCGUGGUGUACGGUCCCAGCAGCGGCGGCAGCUUCCAGCACCCGUCGCAAAUCCAGGAGUUCUACCACGGGCCGUCGUCGCUGUCCACGGCUCCCUACCAGCAGAACCCGUGCGCCGUGGCGUGCCACGGGGACCCCGGCAAUUUCUACGGCUACGACCCGCUGCAACGCCAGAGCCUAUUCGGUGCGCAGGAUCCAGACCUGGUGCAGUACGCAGACUGCAAGCUUGCCGCCGCCAGCGGCCUGGGCGAGGAGGCCGAGGGCUCCGAGCAGAGCCCGUCGCCCACACAGCUCUUCCCCUGGAUGCGCCCGCAAGCAGCCGCCGGACGCAGGCGAGGCCGACAGACCUACAGCCGCUACCAGACCCUGGAGCUGGAGAAGGAGUUCCUAUUUAAUCCCUAUCUGACUCGUAAGCGGCGAAUCGAGGUAUCGCACGCCCUGGGACUGACAGAGAGACAGGUCAAAAUCUGGUUCCAGAACCGGAGGAUGAAGUGGAAAAAAGAGAACAACAAAGACAAGUUCCCCAGCAGCAAAUGCGAGCAGGAGGAGCUGGAGAAACAGAAGCUGGAGCGGGCCCCAGAGGCGGCGGACGAGGGCGACGCGCAGAAGGGCGACAAGAAGUAGGCUUCAGCUGGGACUGCCAGGGCCGCGGCCGCCCGCACGUCCGCGGGUCCCGGCCGCGCCGCCGCCGCGCGCCCCUGCCCGAGAGAGCUCUGGCCCCGCUAGCGGGGCCAGGAGCCGGGCCUCCCACCGCAGCGUCCCCCGCCGCGCCAGUCCCCGCUAGUGGUAGUAUCUCGUAAUAGCUUCUGUGUGUGAGCUACCGUGGAUCUCCUUCCCUUCUCUUGGGGGCCGGGGGGAAAGAAAAGGAUUUAAGCAAAGGCUCCCUCGCCCUGUGAGGGCGAGCGGCAAAGGCCCGGCUGAGCCCCCCAUGCCCCUCCCCUCCCCGUGUAAAAAGCCUCCUUGUGCAAUUGUCUUUUUUUUCCUUUGAACGUGCUUCUUUGUAAUGACCAAGGUACCGAUUUCUGCUAAGUUCUCCCAACAACAUGAAACUGCCUAUUCACGCCGUAAUUCUUUCUGUCUCCCUUCUCUCUCUCUCUCUCGCUCGCUCGCUCUCGCUCUCGCUCUCUCUCGCUGCGUCCUCAUUUCCCCUCCCAAUCCUCUCUCCCCUCUGCAACCCCCCAGCUCGCUGGCUUUCUCUCUGGCUUCUCUCUUUUCCUCCUCCACCCACCCCCUUUGGUUUGACAAUUUUGUCUUAAGUGUUUCUCAAAAGAGGUUACUUUAGUUAGCAUGCGCGCUGUGGGCAAUUGUUACAAGUGUUCUUAGGUUUACUGUGAAGAGAAUGUAUUCUGUAUCCGUGAAUUGCUUUAUGGGGGGGAGGGAGGGCUAAUUAUAUAUUUUGUUGUUCCUCUAUACUUUGUUCUGUUGUCUGCGCCUGAAAAGGGCGGAAGAGUUACAAUAAAGUUUACAAGCGAGAACCCGA